AAGCAGAGGCCGGAAGCGGUGGUUUUUAGCGGCUCUCUGGGUAGCAGGGUGGUGUGAUAGCGGCAGCGAGGGGCUCGGAGAGGUGCUCGGAUUCUCGUAGCUGUGCCGGCCCACAAUGAUUCUGAGCUAAAACACAAAAUAAAAACCAGAUUCAUUGCCACCAGCGCUCACCUCGCCUGACUUAAAAAAAAGUUUCGUACAACAGACACUCCUUGACACCAAGGAUCUUUCACUUAAUCCCUCAAAAAUAAAGACUCGAGCUGGGUGCGGUGGCUCACGCCUGUAAUUCCAGCACUUUGGGAGGCCGAGGCAGGUGGAUCACGAAGUCAGGAGUUCAAGACCAGCCUGCACAAGGUGGUGAAACCCCGUCUCUACUAAAAAUACAAAAAUUAGCUGGGCAUGGUGGUGGGUGCCUGUAAUCCCAGCUACUCCAGAGGCUGAGGCAGAGAAUUGCUUGAACCCUGGAGGUGGAGGUUGAGAUCGCGCCACUGCACUCCACCCUGGGCGACAGAGCAAGACUCCGUCUCAAAAAUAAAUAAAUAAAAAUAAAUAAGUAAAUAAAGACUCGACUUUAUGAUUGAGGAGCUUCGUAAUUUGGAAACCUCAGGUCCUUACCUGGCGAUCUUUGCAUCCUAAAGAAUAAUUACAUUGACAUGAAAUCUUUUCAAUUUAUUUUACCCUAGCUUGCUUUUUGUAAAAAGCAAUUUCAGGGGGGAGGGGGGAGGGAUAGCAUUAGGAGAUAUACCUAAUGUUAAAUGACGAGUUAAUGGGUGCAGCACACCAACAUGGCACAUGUAUACAUAUGUAACCUGCACGUUGUGCACAUGUACCCUAAAACUUAAAGUAUAAUAAUAAAGCAAUUUCAACUUUUUUAGAUUAAGGGGUAUACCCUAGUUUUCUAAACUUCGAUGAGAGUUGUGCAUUUGCUGAAGGCUUAUUACAUGAAGAGUGACAGUCUAAAUUGUUUGAAGGAAAGUAAAAUGAACAACAAACUAGAAUCAGCAAAGAGGACCCUGACAAUAUCAGAAAUGAUCUGCUCCUUGAGAUCAUAGCACUGUUCCUGAUUUGACUCCCUCCACCAUUAUUUAUUCUCCCCACACUUUUAGUUUGGUAGGGAAAAAACCCCACAGUUUCUGUAUUUUGGAACAGUGACUGUGCAGCCAAACUCCCUAUCGCUGAAAGGUUUCUGGUGGAAAAUAACUCAUAGAUCAGAAUCCAGCCUCCUUGAAAAAGUAAAGGCCUAGGUAGUAACUUCCUCAACAUUACACUGCCAGUUUUUGAUAGAAUUAACUACCUUAAUUUGUUAGAAUUGAGACUAACAGCCGAAUCUCUUCAUUCUAACAAUGCUUUGUAGCUUCUAAAUGAUCCCACACGGGGUUUUUCAAGGUCUUCCUCCUCCCCAAUCCCUUAAUUACUCAGAAACAUCUUUUCUGAACUCACAGCAUUUGAUAAUUAUGUACCAUGUUAGGAAUUAUUUUUCAUUAUUGUCACACGUUUUAAGUUUAGAGUCAUACUUCUGGAAUGAAAACUAUGACUCAUUUCAUAAGUUGAACCAAUCAUCUCAUUUCUUUAUAGUUGCCUCCCCAACUAUAUUAAGCUCCUUGAAGAUAGGACACAUGCCUUACAUUUCUUAACUCUUAGCUAGUAUUCAACAUAAUUAAUAUGACGUUUGAUACAUAUUAGUUUAAUUAACUUCAUAAUAAAAUUGAUAAGAUUAAGUAUUGAAUGUGCUGAAGAAGAGCUCUAUAUGAGGCCAUUGUCAGUGCUGACCCAAAAAAAAAAAAAAGCUUUUUUACUUUAAAAAUCUAUUUUAUAAUACAUUUACAAUUCAAAAAAGUGCGUGAUUAAAAGAAUAGGAAAUAUAUCAGAAUUCAGAAAACAUACUACUUUACAACCAAAACUAAGCAUUUUGAAAAUGUAUCUAGAGGACCCUCGUAAAUUUAGUUAUAUGAGAUUUUAUAUAAUAGAUUAAAAAAUCAGAUGUGUCAGCCGUUUGACCUCAUCAGUUUCUUUGUUCUUAAAAUAGCUGACAUUUCUGCAUCAUUAGGGAAAGACAAUGUUGUCACACAAAACAGACUAUUUUUAAAGAUGUGCUUUGGCUUGCAAAGGCGUGACAUGCCUAAAAUAUUAAAGCGAUAUGGACUGGUAAACGUGUCACUCAUUGGGUUUCAACCUCUUGCUCCAAGUCCUUGCGUACAUUUAAGAAUUGGAGGAAUAAUAUAUUCUAUAUCUCUUUGUAUUUUUUAAAGACAGCAUUUAUAACAGACGAGGAAAGUACAUCCUCAUGUAGUUUAGAUGUGAAUGGGAUUUACUACCCCCAAAGGUGUUAUAGAAUGAAAAUAUGCAUUUAUGAAUAGUUUUAAGUCAUGAAAGGCAGCAUCCUAAAAGUUGAUUAAAGAAUUCUAGGAAAUUUGGGAACAGCAUAUAUAUCAUAACUUCUGUGCUAUGUAGGAUAUAUCUUUUCAACAAUAUAUUCCAGUUGCCAUACGGUGCUGUAUUGGAUGGGCUGGAAUUUGUGACUAUCCUUUGUGGAAUUUCCUAUUAAAAUCUGAAAACAGAUUUAGCUUUAAAAAAUUUGAGGCAGAGCUUUUCUAAUCAUUCCAUAAUUGUAUUUAGUCUGGACGAUAUGGUUAUAAUCAAGGAAAGAAUGUAAGAAAUUACUUUUUAAACACAUCGGAAACACAUUCUUAGGGUCACUUUGGAGUGCUGAGAUCUAGGUGGUAGUUCAUUCUUUGCAGUCCACAGACUUAUUUUUAGACCAAUGGCAUAGUGUUUUGCCAGAUCAUAGCUAAAUGUUGUUUUCAGAACGUAAGCUUUAAAAUUGUUAUCCUGGUCAGAGUGAAAUCAGUAGUGCCUAUUUUAGACCUGCUUGGAAGAAUAUAACUCAAUGCAGUGUCUUACUUUUGCUGCUGAGCGGUUUUGCAGACUACCAUCUUCCCUGCAACUCUGAAGGAUGGACUUAACCACCACCAUGUCGAGCAAAAGAACAAAGACCAAGACCAAGAAGCGCCCUCAGCGUGCAACAUCCAAUGUGUUUGCUAUGUUUGACCAGUCACAGAUUCAGGAGUUCAAAGAGGCCUUCAACAUGAUUGAUCAGAACAGAGAUGGUUUCAUCGACAAGGAAGAUUUGCAUGAUAUGCUUGCUUCAUUGGGGAAGAAUCCAACUGAUGAGUAUCUAGAUGCCAUGAUGAAUGAGGCUCCAGGCCCCAUCAAUUUCACCAUGUUCCUCACCAUGUUUGGUGAGAAGUUAAAUGGCACAGAUCCUGAAGAUGUCAUCAGAAAUGCCUUUGCUUGCUUUGAUGAAGAAGCAACUGGCACCAUACAGGAAGAUUACUUGAGAGAGCUGCUGACAACCAUGGGGGAUCGGUUUACAGAUGAGGAAGUGGAUGAGCUGUACAGAGAAGCACCUAUUGAUAAAAAGGGGAAUUUCAAUUACAUCGAGUUCACACGCAUCCUGAAACAUGGAGCCAAAGACAAAGAUGACUGAAAUAACUUCAAAUUCCAGCCAAACGUUCCUUGUUGCCACUUUGGGUAUUCUGAGAUUUUCUCUUGCAUGCCCUUAGCUUUACAGCUUUUGCAUUUCCUGUUGUAUUUAUUCUCAGCCAUUUUGGGCAUAUGUAUCUUUAUAAUCAGACUGGAAACGGGACUUUCUAUUAAUAUCAUUUUCAGAAUAAAAAAUAGGAUAAUUUAACCUACCAGCCCUUCUCCCCCAAUAACUGUGGUCUAUACAGAGUCAAUAUAUUUUUUCAGAGAAAGUUAUUCGCUCGAUUUUUUCUGAAUCAUAAUUAAACUUUAUGAUAAAAUAC